ACAGAGCAGUGAUAACUACCUGCCAGUGUCUCUUAGGAGUGAGGUACCUGGAGUUCGGGGACCCCAACCUGUGACAAUGACAGCAGACAAAUUGGUUUUCUUUGUGAAUGGCAGAAAGGUGGUGGAGAAAAAUGCAGAUCCAGAGACAACCCUUUUGGCCUACCUGAGAAGAAAGUUGGGGCUGAGUGGAACCAAGCUCGGCUGUGGAGAGGGGGGCUGCGGGGCUUGCACAGUGAUGCUCUCCAAGUAUGAUCGUCUGCAGAACAAGAUCGUCCACUUUUCUGCCAAUGCCUGCCUGGCCCCCAUCUGCUCCUUGCACCAUGUUGCAGUGACAACUGUGGAAGGAAUAGGAAGCACCAAGACGAGGCUGCAUCCUGUGCAGGAGAGAAUUGCCAAAAGCCACGGCUCCCAGUGCGGGUUCUGCACCCCUGGCAUCGUCAUGAGUAUGUACACACUGCUCCGGAAUCAGCCCGAGCCCACCAUGGAGGAGAUUGAGAAUGCCUUCCAAGGAAAUCUGUGCCGCUGCACAGGCUACAGACCCAUCCUCCAGGGCUUCCGGACCUUUGCCAGGGAUGGUGGAUGCUGUGGAGGAGAUGGGAAUAAUCCAAAUUGCUGCAUGAACCAGAAGAAAGACCACUCAGUCAGCCUCUCGCCAUCUUUAUUCAAACCAGAGGAGUUCACGCCCCUGGAUCCAACCCAGGAGCCCAUUUUUCCCCCAGAGUUGCUGAGGCUGAAAGACACUCCUCGGAAGCAGCUGCGAUUUGAAGGGGAGCGUGUGACGUGGAUACAGGCCUCAACCCUCAAGGAGCUGCUGGACCUCAAGGCUCAGCACCCUGACGCCAAGCUGGUCGUGGGGAACACGGAGAUUGGCAUUGAGAUGAAGUUCAAGAAUAUGCUGUUUCCUAUGAUUGUCUGCCCAGCCUGGAUCCCUGAGCUGAAUUCGGUAGAACAUGGACCCGACGGUAUCUCCUUUGGAGCUGCUUGCCCCCUGAGCAUUGUGGAAAAAACCCUGGUGGAUGCUGUUGCUAAGCUUCCUGCCCAAAAGACAGAGGUGUUCAGAGGGGUCCUGGAGCAGCUGCGCUGGUUUGCUGGGAAGCAAGUCAAGUCUGUGGCGUCCGUUGGAGGGAACAUCAUCACUGCCAGCCCCAUCUCCGACCUCAACCCCGUGUUCAUGGCCAGUGGGGCCAAGCUGACACUUGUGUCCAGAGGCACCAGGAGAACUGUCCAGAUGGACCACACCUUCUUCCCUGGCUACAGAAAGACCCUGCUGAGCCCGGAGGAGAUACUGCUCUCCAUAGAGAUCCCCUACAGCAGGGAGGGGGAGUAUUUCUCAGCAUUCAAGCAGGCCUCCCGGAGAGAAGAUGACAUUGCCAAGGUAACCAGUGGCAUGAGAGUUUUAUUCAAGCCAGGAACCACAGAGGUACAGGAGCUGGCCCUUUGCUAUGGUGGAAUGGCCAACAGAACCAUCUCAGCCCUCAAGACCACUCAGAGGCAGCUUUCCAAGCUCUGGAAGGAGGAGCUGCUGCAGGACGUGUGUGCAGGACUGGCAGAGGAGCUGCAUCUGCCUCCCGAUGCCCCUGGUGGCAUGGUGGACUUCCGGUGCACCCUCACCCUCAGCUUCUUCUUCAAGUUCUACCUGACAGUCCUUCAGAAGCUGGGCCAAGAGAACCUGGAAGACAAGUGUGGUAAACUGGACCCCACUUUCGCCAGUGCAACUUUACUGUUUCAGAAAGACCCCCCAGCCGAUGUCCAGCUCUUCCAAGAGGUGCCCAAGGGUCAGUCUGAGGAGGACAUGGUGGGCCGGCCCCUGCCCCACCUGGCAGCGGACAUGCAGGCCUCUGGUGAGGCCGUGUACUGUGACGACAUUCCUCGCUACGAGAAUGAGCUGUCUCUCCGGCUGGUCACCAGCACCCGGGCCCACGCCAAGAUCAAGUCCAUAGAUACAUCAGAAGCUAAGAAGGUUCCAGGGUUUGUUUGUUUCAUUUCCGCUGAUGAUGUUCCUGGGAGUAACAUAACUGGAAUUUGUAAUGAUGAGACAGUCUUUGCGAAGGAUAAGGUUACUUGUGUUGGGCAUAUCAUUGGUGCUGUGGUUGCUGACACCCCGGAACACACACAGAGAGCUGCCCAAGGGGUGAAAAUCACCUAUGAAGAACUACCAGCCAUUAUCACAAUUGAGGAUGCUAUAAAGAACAACUCCUUUUAUGGACCUGAGCUGAAGAUCGAGAAAGGGGACCUAAAGAAGGGGUUUUCCGAAGCAGAUAAUGUUGUGUCAGGGGAGAUAUACAUCGGUGGCCAAGAGCACUUCUACCUGGAGACUCACUGCACCAUUGCUGUUCCAAAAGGCGAGGCAGGGGAGAUGGAGCUCUUUGUGUCUACACAGAACACCAUGAAGACCCAGAGCUUUGUUGCAAAAAUGUUGGGGGUUCCAGCAAACCGGAUUGUGGUUCGAGUGAAGAGAAUGGGAGGAGGCUUUGGAGGCAAGGAGACCCGGAGCACUGUGGUGUCCACGGCAGUGGCCCUGGCUGCAUAUAAGACCGGCCGCCCUGUGCGAUGCAUGCUGGACCGUGAUGAGGACAUGCUGAUAACUGGUGGCAGACAUCCCUUCCUGGCCAGAUACAAGGUUGGCUUCAUGAAGACUGGGACAGUUGUGGCUCUUGAGGUGGACCACUUCAGCAAUGUGGGGAACACCCAGGAUCUCUCUCAGAGUAUUAUGGAACGAGCUUUAUUCCACAUGGACAACUGCUAUAAAAUCCCCAACAUCCGGGGCACUGGGCGGCUGUGCAAAACCAACCUUCCCUCCAACACGGCCUUCCGGGGCUUUGGGGGGCCCCAGGGGAUGCUCAUUGCCGAGUGCUGGAUGAGUGAAGUUGCAGUGACCUGUGGGAUGCCUGCAGAGGAGGUGCGGAGAAAAAACCUGUACAAAGAAGGGGACCUGACACACUUCAACCAGAAGCUUGAGGGUUUCACCUUGCCCAGAUGCUGGGAAGAAUGCCUAGCAAGCUCUCAGUAUCAUGCUCGGAAGAGUGAGGUUGACAAGUUCAACAAGGAGAAUUGUUGGAAAAAGAGAGGAUUGUGCAUAAUUCCCACCAAGUUUGGAAUAAGCUUUACAGUUCCUUUUCUGAAUCAGGCAGGAGCCCUACUUCAUGUGUACACAGAUGGCUCUGUGCUGCUGACCCACGGGGGGACUGAGAUGGGCCAAGGCCUUCAUACCAAAAUGGUCCAGGUGGCCAGUAGAGCUCUGAAAAUCCCCACCUCUAAGAUUUAUAUCAGCGAGACAAGCACUAACACUGUGCCCAACACCUCUCCCACGGCUGCCUCUGUCAGCGCUGACCUCAAUGGACAGGCCGUCUAUGCGGCUUGUCAGACCAUCUUGAAAAGGCUGGAACCCUACAAGAAGAAGAAUCCCAGUGGCUCCUGGGAAGACUGGGUCACAGCUGCCUACAUGGACACAGUGAGCUUGUCUGCCACUGGGUUUUAUAGAACACCCAAUCUGGGCUACAGCUUUGAGACUAACUCAGGGAACCCCUUCCACUACUUCAGCUAUGGGGUGGCUUGCUCUGAAGUAGAAAUCGACUGCCUAACAGGAGAUCAUAAGAACCUCCGCACAGAUAUUGUCAUGGAUGUUGGCUCCAGUCUAAACCCUGCCAUUGAUAUUGGACAGGUGGAAGGGGCAUUUGUCCAGGGCCUUGGCCUCUUCACCCUAGAGGAGCUACACUAUUCCCCCGAGGGGAGCCUGCACACCCGUGGCCCUAGCACCUACAAGAUCCCGGCAUUUGGCAGCAUCCCCAUUGAGUUCAGGGUGUCCCUGCUCCGCGACUGCCCCAACAAGAAGGCCAUCUAUGCAUCGAAGGCUGUUGGAGAGCCGCCCCUCUUCCUGGCUGCUUCUAUCUUCUUUGCCAUCAAAGAUGCCAUCCGUGCAGCUCGAGCUCAGCACACAGGUAAUAACGUGAAGGAACUCUUCCGGCUAGACAGCCCUGCCACCCCGGAGAAGAUCCGCAAUGCCUGCGUGGACAAGUUCACCACCCUGUGUGUCACUGGUGUCCCAGAAAACUGCAAACCCUGGUCUGUGAGGGUCUAAAGAGAGAGUCCUCAGCAGAGUCUUCUUGUGCUGCCUUUGGGCUUCCAUGGAGCAGGAGGAACAUACCACAGAACAUGGAUCUAUUAAAGUCACAGAAUGACAGACCUGUGAUUUGUCAAGAUGGGAUUUGGAAGACAAGUGAAUGCAAUGGAAGAUUUUGAUCAAAAAUGUAAUUUGUAAACACAAUGAUAAGCAAAUUCAAAACUGUUAUGCCUAAAUGGUGAAUAUGCAAUUAGGAUCAUUUUCUGUCUGUUUUAAUCAUGUAUCUGGAAUAGGGUCGGGAAGGGUUUGUGCUAUUCCCCACUUACUGGACAGCCUGUAUAACCUCAAGUUCUGAUGGUGUCUGUCCUUUGAAGAGGAUUCCCACAAACCUCUAGAAGCUUAAACCGAAGUUACUUUAAAUCGUGUGCCUUCCUGUGAAAGCCUGGCCUUCAAACCAAUGAACAGCAAAGCAUAACCUUGAAUCUAUACUCAAAUUUUGCAAUGAGGCAGUGGGGUAAGGUUAAAUCCUCUAACCAUCUUUGAAUCAUUGGAAAGAAUAAAGAAUGAAACAAAUUCAAGGUUAAUUGGAUCUGAUUUUGUGAAGCUGCAUAAAGCAAGAUUACUCUAUAAUACAAAAAUCCAACCAACUCAAUUAUUGAGCACGUACAAUGUUCUAGAUUUCUUUCCCUUCCUCUUUGAAGAGAAUAUUUGUAUUCCAAAUACUCUUUGAGUAUUUACAAAAAAGAUUAUGUUUAAUCUUUACAUUUGAAGCCAAAGUAAUUUCCACCUAGAAAUGAUGCUAUCAGUCCUGGCAUGGUGGCUCACCCCUAUAAUCCCAGCACUUUGGGAGGCUAAGGCAGGAGAAUUGCUUGAGCCCAGCAGUUUGAGACCAGCCUGGGCAACAUAGAGAGCUCCUGUCUUUAAAAAAAAUUUUUUUAAUUAGUUGGUCUUGAUAGUGCAUGCCUGUAGUCCCAACUACUUGAAAGGCUGAGGUGGAGAGAUCAUUUGAGCUCAGGAGGUUGAGGCUGCAGUGAGCUAUGAUUGCGCCACUGCACUCCUGCCUGAGCGACUGAGCAAGAUCUUGUCUCUGAAGAAAAAAAAAGAAAUAAAAAUGCUGCUAUCAAAAUCAAGCCCAACCAGAGGUAGAAGAGCCAAGAAGCCUGGGUUCUCAUCCUAGCUCUGUCUCUUCUGUCUCUAUCUUUGUGAUCUUGGACUGUCAAUUCCCCUUCCUGUGAUCCAUUUUACUGCAAACAUAAGGGUUGCAGUAAAGGGUUGUCUCACGUCUUCUGCUUUAAAAGCCUAUAAAUAUAUGACCUGAAAACUCCAGUUACAUAAAGGAUCUGCAGCUAUCUAAGGCUUGGUUUUCUUACUGUCAUAUGAUACCUGGGUCUAAUGAACUCUGCUGAGAUCACCUCAAGUUUCUGCGGUUGGUAAAGAGAACAAGGGAAGAACAAACAUCCCUUUUAUUGCUCCAAAUGGUGAUUUAAUCCCUACAUGGUGCUGGGUGGACAAUGUGUCACUGUCACAUGCCUUCACUGUAUAAAUCCAACCUUCUGCCAGAGAGAAUCUGUGGUUCUGGCCAUGGAGGGAGGAUAGUGGAAAUGAUAUAGUUGGACUGGUGCUUGAUGUCACUAAUAAAUGAAACUGUCAGCUGG